CCAGCCUGGGCGACAGUGUGAGACUUCAUCUAAAAAAAAAAAAAUUUGGCUGGAUACCUCCUGACUGCAGGAUAUAGUCGAAUUCCAAACCGUAGAUAGCAUAGAGGGUUCUUCAUAAUUUGACCUUACUAGCAUUAUUUUUUUCUUUUUCCUUCUAAUCUAUUCACCAGUUGUAUCAGUCAGUUAAUGCUAUGUAACAAACUCUCAAAACUAAGGGCUUAGUACCAAACAAUAUUACUAUAGCUCUCACCUUUGUGGAUUGGCUGGAGUCAGCUAAUCUAGGCUGGGUUCUAUUCUGGCUGGAGACUUUAGCUUGGUCAGCUCUGUUCCAUGUGGCACAUUUAGACCAGAGACCUCCAUGCAAUUUUAUCCCCCUGGAACUAGUGGAUUGACUAGGCAUGCACUUCUCAUAGUAACAGAAGAAGUUCAAAAGAGCAACCUGCAAGCUCUUGAGUCCUAGGGUAGGAAUUGGCGCAUCGUUACUUUUGGCCCAUUUUACUGGCUAAAGCAAUAAAAUGGAUAAAUCCAGAGACUCAUGGAUACAUCCAGAGUCAGGAGGCAGAAAAAUAAACUUUGCCUCUUGAUGGAAAAAAUCUGCAAAGUCACAUGGCAAAAGGUGUGGACAGAGUGAGAGGUGAAAAAUUGAGGCUGUUAAUACAAAAUUUACCACACCAGCAAUCCACUGAAUUUUAAAAUUUCCUGAACAUACCAUGUCUGUUUAUGAAAGGGAUGAUAAGGAUUCAUUCCAGGUCAUUGAGUCAUGAGGAAGCUUGGAAAGUUUAUUAUUGCUUAAAGACUGUCGUGAUGUCUCUUGCUUCUUGGUUCUGUGACUUCUUUGGUCCUUCCCUCACUGAUUCUGUUAAUCCAGACAGCCUUUCCAUACCACCUACAUGAUAAGAGUCUGUUUCUGAUGCUUCCAACUGAAAACCUUGACUGAAUAGCUUGAUAACUUGAAUAAUCUCAUUGCUUCUGCCCAAAGAUUGUCUUUCUUGCAAAGUGAGAGAAGAGAAAUGAAAGAAGUGAAUAAUGUGGUAAAAGUUUCCACACCUUCAUAUAAAUGAAAUUAAUGGAGUGAUUUCCUUUUUGAAUUAGAAUCUGGCUGUGAGCAAAACCAUGUUAGAGAACCAAAUAAGCACACAACCAUGGGGCUCAUCACUACCCCUUGGAAGUGCAUCUGGGGAUGGGGAGUGAGGGAGCCAAUGUGAAGAUGCUUUCCAUCCUAACCCUGUUUGAGUACAGUAAGUGGCACGUGUGCACCUGCCCCAGGGGAAGAGAAAGGAUCUCAAAAUCAAUCUAAGGAGUGUUUCUCCACUUGCAGUUCUCUUUGUAUCCACUGGACACAUUUAGUUUCUACUUCUUUCUUAAGAACUAUUUUAAGGAAGUGCUGCCUUCUAUUCUAAAUAUAAUAUUCCCCUUCCUUGCCCGAACUCCUUGGUACAAGUUUACUUUGUGCCUCUCUUACGACAUGUAUUAUUGUUAUUUAUCUACACAUCAAUAUAUAUGUUCAUCUAGGCUGUGACUACCUUAGUGAUCAUAAUAGACUUUUGUCUUUCUAUUUUUAGUAGGAUGGAUCAAAUGAAUGCUGAAUUUGUUUUAUAAGACCAUAAUCUGGAGGCAAGAUUAUUUAUCUUUUGCUUUUUCAUCCUUCACAUCACCUCAUAUAAUUCCUUGGACUUAGAAGUCACUCUAUAAAUAAAUAUUUGUUGAAUGAUGUAAACAAAAAUAUGCUUACUCUUGAGGCUCUGAAUUUUAUUAUUGAAGUAUUUAUUUAUGUUAUUAAAUCCUCUGUGAGAUUAGGAGGCUUAAGAGAAUAUUCUUAUGGAUUCUUCUUAAAAUUUAUCAUUUCCUCUCCCAGAUCCAUACGAGAAAAAUUUGGAGGAGAUGGAAUUUAGUAUGGAGAAGAGAUGACUGAUGGCUGAUUAUUAAUGCUCUUUCACAGGAUAUUUCUUUAAUGGGAAAAAUGUACCUCAAAACAUCACCUAUGCAAGCAGAAACACCUGAGAUACAAGCAGAGUAUAAAUUCCAGAUGGGUGCUGAGGAAUCGCAAAUGAGCGUGCAUAAGGAACUUUCUGAAACCAUGUCAAGUAUUCUCCAGAUUGAACAAGAGGAUAUAGAAUGGGGACCCUCAGAAGCAGAAAGCAUAGUAUUUAAACCUCAGGAAAUUUCGCAAGUUCAGCCAGCAGAGGAAUUAAGUAAACCUUUGGAAGAUGGACAGCCCACAAGUGAUUCAAAAGAAGCCAAGUGGGUGUCUUUAACGGCAAAAUCACCAGAAUUCUUGCAAAUCGAAGGAAAAGAAAUUAAGCGAAUGCGGAAACGUAAAUCACUGAGACCAAGAAAGUCUUCAAAACCUCUUUGUGAUAAAAAACUACAUAAAAAAAUUCCACAAGACUACUCCAUGCCGCACCUUCAUGAUCUGUGCACCACCAUCCCAGCCCAGGAGCUGCCUGUUGACUUGCGCCUGGCUUCUCGAGUGUAUCACACUGCUAACAGGAAAGGCCACGAUACCCUGCUUGGAAAAUUUGGAACCUCUUUCUUAGAUGAUCGCUUUACAGAUGAAGAACAAACAGAUAGAAUAUUGUAUGGAAUUCCUGUUAUGGAUGACAACCAAGAAUAUGUCCAUAUUCCUCCGACACCGCAAGGGAUACCACCUGAAUUGGCACAAGGAACUAGAGAGCGUGCUCACAAACCACACUUGGAAGUCUUGGGAGAGGAAAUGUAUGCUUAUCCAGAAUUCACGAAGUUGUUUUGGAAUACAGCUGCACCUAAAUUCUCUGUUCCAGAAUCUGUCAUGAAGGAAACUCUAUAUCCAAAAUAUGAGAGUGUUCAAGCAAGCAGACUUUUAACUGAUAAAUUGUCAUAUAAAAGCAGUGUCAUUACUUUACAUCAACAUAGCAGAACAAAUUUUUGGUGUUUCUUACCAAGAAAAUCUGCAUCAUUUGAAAGUAUCCAAAAAUGGUUUAGUGCACAACCUACACAACUAAGGCGAGUAAAAUCUUCUGUAGACUUGAGGAAGGAGAAGAUCAUAGCUCCUUUGGAAAUCAAGAAUGAUAUGCAAAGCAGUAUAAAAGAGGUUAUGUUUCAGAAAGCAAAGGAAUUGAAACGUCAGCUCCAGCUCACUAAGCAAAAUAAAACUGAGGAGCCCAACUAUGUGAAAGAAAGUAUAGAUGACAUCUUUGAUAACAUGUGCGAAAAACACAGUUUGAGAAAUCUCUCUUUGACUCUCAUUGAAGCGUCUAAAAAAGCUGGCAUUAGUUACAUUGUUUAUCCCAAGAAAAAGAAGAUGAGAUGGAAGAAAAGAUUGAAACAACAAAAACUUAUAUUCGUGCAUGAAGAGUUAUCCAAGCCUCCAAAAUCUCUUGAAAGAUCAGCAUCUCAUGGAAUACUUCCGGGACAGAAGAAAUAUUUGUUCAAAGUUCCAUUAUAUGAACGUCAAAUACGGUGUCCCAGUUUACCUUUGUAUUUAAAUUUUGAAAAAUUCGUCCAAGCUAAGGGAGGAAUUCCAGAAAAUAUUGAUCCUCGGACAUGGGCUCUUGAUAGGCUCAUUGAGUACAAAGAUGCGAGCAUACCUGUAAAAGAGAAAGAUGAUAAAAUAUCAGUUCCUGAAGACCCACCUGAAAGAGUGAAAGAACCACCAAAACUAAAAUUAAAUGAUUAUGUGGAGUCUGAUCUUCCACAAGAGGUCAUUAAAUAUUAUGAAUCUGAAGUGAAGAUUUUGACUGAAGAAAUAAAUGAUAAGACAAAAUAUCCUGCAUUUGCAUAUUGUAGGCGUGGAGCUAUUUAUAGGAAACUGGGAAAGUUGCAGAGUGCCAUGAAUGAUCUGCAGAGAGUAAUACUCUUGGAACCAUUGUUUCUCAAUGCCUAUUGGCAUCGACAUUUAAUUUAUCUUUUCCAAGACAAAAUUAAUGAAGCUUUGGAUGACUUGAAUUAUAUACAUAAAUAUAAUAAAAAUAAUACAGAGGCAUAUUUGUCAAAAGCAGAAAUUUACAGGGGAAAAAAAGACAUAACUUUGGCAAUUCUAAACUAUACCCAGGCAAUUAAAUCCACGCCCACAGAUGCUGAUAUCUAUUUCAGGAGGGGUGAGAUGUAUGAAAUAACAAACAAAGUACUGGCCAUUGAUGACUUUUCGAAAUGUAUUUUUUAUGAUCCCAAAAGAACAGAUGCAUUAUUGAAACGUGGGCUGUUUUAUUGUGAAAAUGAAAACUGGUUUGCAGCCAUAGAGGAUUUUACAGCCUUGUUAAAUAUAGAUCACCAAAAUUCUCAAGCAAGGACAUACCGAGGGAUUGCAUAUGUUAAAUGGAAAUUUUAUAAAGAAGCAACUCAAGAUUUUUCUGCUGCAAUUCACUUAGAUCCUAAUAACUGGUUAGCGUUGUAUUAUCGAGGUUGCUUAUUCAGAAAGAGUAACCCUUUUAGAGCGCUACAGGAUUAUAGUGUUUCAGCACUCAUAAAUGAUGGCUAUGAGAAUCUUGGUUGUUUUCUACAUCGGGGAAUAGUCUAUGCACAUCUAAAACUUUGGCUGCUGGCAAUUUGUGACUUUGAAACUGUCAUUUCUCUAGAAAGAACUAUUACUUUGGCUUAUGUAAAUAUUGGCCUCAUACAUCUGCUACACCUGGAUAACUACACGGAAGCUAUUUGGCAAUUUUCUGAGGCUAUUAGAAUUGAUCCUUUAUGUAUUCAAAGCUAUCUUUGUCGGGCGGAAACCUAUUUUAAGUUGCAUAAAUUGAAAAAGGCAGUAAAUGAAUUGUCUCGUGCUAUCCACCUUCAGCCAGAUGGAAUCCAAUUAUACAUAAGAAGAGGACAAUAUCUUCUUAUGAUGAAAUAUUAUGAUCUUGCAAAGUUUACUAUUUAUCAAAUAGCAGAAAUGGACAAAGGUCUCAGUGAGUUGAGUCCUAUGCAGCAAGCCCUUAUUUAUUCAUUUUGUGAAAACCAUGACAAGGCCAUUGAGGUCUUGGACGGAAUCAGCUGGAAUAGAGCUGAGAUGACCAUGUGUGCUCUAUUAGCAAAAGUUCAAAUGAAGGCCAAGAGAACCAAGGAAGCUGUGGAAGUGCUUAAGAAGGCUUUGGAUGCCAUUUCUCAUUCUGAUAAAGGACCAGAUGCCACAGCAAUUUCAGCAGACUGUCUGUAUAACUUGGGUCUUUGUUACAUGGAGGAAGGCAAUUUACAAAUGGCUUUUGAUUCUUUUACAAAAGCUGUGAAAGCAAAUCCAGAUUUUGCAGAAAGCUUUUAUCAGCGAGGGCUUUGUAAAGUGAAACUCCACAAGGAUAGCUCGAUUCUGGAUUUUAAUCGUGCAAUUACCCUCAAUCCAAAACAUUACCAGGAGAUGCAUACUGGAGGACUUGGGGCAUAUUUAAGCCGAGUAGCAUUCUAUGGUUUAAAAGGCAGGUAUUCCAAAGCAAUCUUGAAUUGUAACAAGGCUAUUAAAAUUUACCCUGAAAGCGUACGUGCCUAUCUCUACAGAGGAGUUCUGAAAUACUACAACAAGACUUAUAAGCUAGCAAUUACAGAUUUAACUACAGCUAUCAGCAUGGACAAAAAUAGUUAUACAGCAUUUUAUAACAGAGCAUUAUGUUACACCAAGAUAAGGGAACUUCAAAUGGCAUUAACAGAUUAUGGAAUUGUGCUGCUUCUUGAUGCUACAGAAACUGUAAAACUAAAUACCUUCCUUAAUCGUGGACUCAUCUACGUAGAACUAGGCCAGUAUGGCUUUGCACUAGAGGAUUUUAAACAAGCUGCACUGAUAAGCCGGACUAACGGGAGCCUUUGUCACGCCACUGCCAUGUGCCAUCACAGAAUUAAUGAGUUUGAAGAAGCUGUCAAUUUCUUUACUUGGGCUCUUAAAAUUAACCCAUGUUUUCUGGAUGCUUAUGUUGGACGGGGAAAUUCUUACAUGGAAUACGGUCAUGAUGAAGCCACCAAGCAAGCACAGAAAGACUUUCUGAAAGCACUGCAUAUUAAUCCAGCAUACAUAAAAGCCAGAAUUAGUUUUGGCUAUAAUUUGCAGGCCCAAGGAAAAUUCCAGAAAGCUUGGAACCACUUUACCAUUGCCAUAGAUACUGAUCCAAAGAACUACCUAGCCUAUGAAGGAAGAGCUGUGGUCUGUCUUCAGAUGGGUAAUAAUUUUGCUGCAAUGCAGGAUAUUAAUGCUGCCAUGAAGAUCAGUACUACAGCAGAAUUCUUAACAAAUCGUGGGGUGAUUCAUGAGUUUAUGGGCCACAAACAGAAUGCAAUGAAAGACUACCAAGAUGCAAUUACUCUAAACCCCAAGUACUCGCUGGCUUACUUUAAUGCAGGAAAUAUCUACUUUCACCACAGGCAGUUUUCCCAGGCCAGUGACUACUUCUCAAAAGCUUUAAAAUUUGAUCCAGAAAAUGAAUAUGUUCUCAUGAAUCGAGCUAUUACAAAUACAAUAUUAAAGAAAUAUGAAGAAGCAAAAGAAGAUUUUGCAAAUGUAAUUGAAAGCUGUCCCUUUUGGGCUGCAGUAUAUUUUAAUAGAGCACAUUUCUACUACUGCUUAAAGCAAUAUGAACUAGCUGAGGAAGACCUUAAUAAAGCCCUGUCUUUGAAGCCUAAUGAUGCUCUAGUAUAUAAUUUUAGAGCAAAAGUUCGUGGUAAAAUAGGUCUGAUUGAGGAAGCUAUGGCUGACUAUAACCAAGCACUUGAUCUUGAAGACUAUGCCUCAGUUAUAUGAUUACAUAGACUGUGGUUGCUAUAGUAGUUUACACAGCUGUUCUCUCUGAAACGGAAACAUAUUUGUUGUCUAAAAGGUUCUACCAUUUUCAUUAUUGUAUUCGUUAUGCUUAGUCUUCCAUAUAACCUUCUAUGCAUUUUAAUAAAAUGUUUGUUAUACAUUAAUUAUAAAACAUAUAUCAUUUGCUGCAUAUUUGGAAUACCUUGAGAACUGAAUUUUUCCAAGGUUGCAGAAUCUCAAGGAAAAUGUUUCUUAAGGAAUUAAAUAGGAAUGUCUCUUAACAUUUAAAAUAUUUUCUUUAAUUCUUUUUGAAAUAAUACUAUACAUUGUAGAAAAAGUGUCACUGACCUUUUCAUCAAUCCUUGCUGACAAUGUAUUAAACAGUAUACAGAUUAAAAAAUAAACCGAUGACUAUAAAAAACUGAA